AGCAACUUGCUGGAGUCGCCUUCUGUGCUGUGGAAGUUUUGUUGUUUUGCUUGUUUGCAAUAACCGUUGCUGCUGCUUACUGUUUGGGUCCGCACUGCCUUUAUGAGCUGUAACGCUCACCGUGAAGGUCUGCAGCUUCGUUCUUAAAGCCAGCCACAUCACGGACCCACCGGGAGAAACGAAUAACUCCAAACACGCCACCUUAAGAGCCGUAGCACUCAUGAUGAAGGUCCGUAGCUUCACUCCUGAAGUCAGCGAGAUCACGAAUCUGCCAGAAGGAAGAAACUCCGAACACAUGCGAGCAUCAGAAGAAACAAACUUGGGACACGCUGCCUUUAAAAACUGUAACACUCACCGCCAGGGUCCGCGGCUUCGUUCUUGAAGUCAGUGAGACCAAGAAUCCGCCGAUUCUGGACACACCAUGACGGAACUAGAUCCUUGGCCUUUCGGGGCCCAGAACGCUACGGACGCCGGGCGGCCAGGAGGGGUUGGGCUCCCGCUCCACCCCGGUCCCCGGCGAGCACGCGGCCAGGCAGAGAAGGUGCCCGGAGCUCAGAGCGCGCAGAGCCCGGCCGCUGGGCCGCUGCCUGAGCCAGGGAGGCGCAGCGCGAGCUCCCACUUCGUCUUCAUGGAUUCCCAGCCCAGCUGCGUGGUGGUGACUGGAGCUCUCCAAGCUGGGCCUGGGGAAUGAAACAGUGGUGCAGCUGCGGACUCUGGAGCUGCCUGUAGAUUACAGGGAGGCUAAGCGGAGGGUCACCGGAAUCUGGGAAGAUCAUCAGCCGCAACUCGUCGUGCAUGUGGGCAUGGACACCGCCGCCAAGGCGAUCAUUCUGGAACAGUCUGGCAAGAACCAAGGCUACCGGGACGCCGACAUCCGCAGCUUCUGGCCCGAGGGCGGCGUGUGCCUACCUGGCAGCCCAGACGUGCUGGAGUCAGGGGUCUGCAUGAAGGCAGUCUGCAAGCGCGUAGCUGUGGAGGGUGUCGACGUGAUCUUUUCCCGAGAUGCAGGCAGAUACGUCUGUGAUUAUACCUAUUACCUGUCUCUGCAUCAUGGAAAGGGCUGCGCGGCACUCAUCCAUGUCCCUCCACUAUCGCGCGGGCUCCCGGCCAGCCUGCUGGGAAGAGCCUUGAGAGUCAUCAUCCAGGAAAUGCUGGAAGAGGUGGGAAAGCCCAAGCACAGAGCCCAGUUCGAAGAAAACUCAACCAUGGUCCUUCCAGCCAAAGGGAACUGACCGGGGGAUUGCUCCUCUAGAGAAAAUUGAAUGUUUCAAUCCUGUAUGUAGCACUCAACUGUGCAUUGAGAAACUUUUUCAAAAAUUGCUUGUAAGACAAAGAGGGUGGAAAACUCUGAAUUAGCCCAACAAAAUCACAAAGGGUUAUUUUAUUGUCAGGAGAAAGAACACUCUGAAAGGUGGACAUUUCACAGGGGAUGAACUAGCUUCAGUUAUGGUUUUCAUGACAAUAAAAUGAAAUCCGAGUCA